AUACCACAGCCUUCAUCUGCGCCCUGGGGCCAGGACUGCUGCUGUCACUGCCAUCCAUUGGAGCCCAGCACCCCCUCCCCGCCCAUCCUUCGGACAGCAACUCCAGCCCAGCCCCGCGUCCCUGUGUCCACUUCUCCUGACCCCUCGGCCGCCACCCCAGAAGGCUGGAGCAGGGACGCCGUCGCUCCGGCCGCCUGCUCCCCUCGGGUCCCCGUGCGAGCCCACGCCGGCCCCGGUGCCCGCCCGCAGCCCUGCCACUGGACACAGGAUAAGGCCCAGCGCACAGGCCCCCACGUGGACAGCAUGGACCGCGGCACGCUCCCUCUGGCUGUUGCCCUGCUGCUGGCCAGCUGCAGCCUCAGCCCCACAAGUCUUGCAGAAACAGUCCAUUGUGACCUUCAGCCUGUGGGCCCCGAGAGGGGCGAGGUGACAUAUACCACUAGCCAGGUCUCGAAGGGCUGCGUGGCUCAGGCCCCCAAUGCCAUCCUUGAAGUCCAUGUCCUCUUCCUGGAGUUCCCAACGGGCCCGUCACAGCUGGAGCUGACUCUCCAGGCAUCCAAGCAAAAUGGCACCUGGCCCCGAGAGGUGCUUCUGGUCCUCAGUGUAAACAGCAGUGUCUUCCUGCAUCUCCAGGCCCUGGGAAUCCCACUGCACUUGGCCUACAAUUCCAGCCUGGUCACCUUCCAAGAGCCCCCGGGGGUCAACACCACAGAGCUGCCAUCCUUCCCCAAGACCCAGAUCCUUGAGUGGGCAGCUGAGAGGGGCCCCAUCACCUCUGCUGCUGAGCUGAAUGACCCCCAGAGCAUCCUCCUCCGACUGGGCCAAGCCCAGGGGUCACUGUCCUUCUGCAUGCUGGAAGCCAGCCAGGACAUGGGCCGCACGCUCGAGUGGCGGCCGCGUACUCCAGCCUUGGUCCGGGGCUGCCACUUGGAAGGCGUGGCCGGCCACAAGGAGGCGCACAUCCUGAGGGUCCUGCCGGGCCACUCGGCCGGGCCCCGGACGGUGACGGUGAAGGUGGAACUGAGCUGCGCACCCGGGGAUCUCGAUGCCGUCCUCAUCCUGCAGGGUCCCCCCUACGUGUCCUGGCUCAUCGACGCCAACCACAACAUGCAGAUCUGGACCACUGGAGAAUACUCCUUCAAGAUCUUUCCAGAGAAAAACAUUCGUGGCUUCAAGCUCCCAGACACACCUCAAGGCCUCCUGGGGGAGGCCCGGAUGCUCAAUGCCAGCAUUGUGGCAUCCUUCGUGGAGCUACCGCUGGCCAGCAUUGUCUCACUUCAUGCCUCCAGCUGCGGUGGUAGGCUGCAGACCUCACCCGCACCGAUCCAGACCACUCCUCCCAAGGACACUUGUAGCCCGGAGCUGCUCAUGUCCUUGAUCCAGACAAAGUGUGCCGACGACGCCAUGACCCUGGUACUAAAGAAAGAGCUUGUUGCGCAUUUGAAGUGCACCAUCACGGGCCUGACCUUCUGGGACCCCAGCUGUGAGGCAGAGGACAGGGGUGACAAGUUUGUCUUGCGCAGUGCUUACUCCAGCUGUGGCAUGCAGGUGUCAGCAAGUAUGAUCAGCAAUGAGGCGGUGGUCAAUAUCCUGUCGAGCUCAUCACCACAGCGGAAAAAGGUGCACUGCCUCAACAUGGACAGCCUCUCUUUCCAGCUGGGCCUCUACCUCAGCCCACACUUCCUCCAGGCCUCCAACACCAUCGAGCCGGGGCAGCAGAGCUUUGUGCAGGUCAGAGUGUCCCCAUCCGUCUCCGAGUUCCUGCUCCAGUUAGACAGCUGCCACCUGGACUUGGGGCCUGAGGGAGGCACCGUGGAACUCAUCCAGGGCCGGGCGGCCAAGGGCAACUGUGUGAGCCUGCUGUCCCCAAGCCCCGAGGGUGACCCGCGCUUCAGCUUCCUCCUCCACUUCUACACAGUACCCAUACCCAAAACCGGCACCCUCAGCUGCACGGUAGCCCUGCGUCCCAAGACCGGGUCUCAAGACCAGGAAGUCCAUAGGACUGUCUUCAUGCGCUUGAACAUCAUCAGCCCUGACCUGUCUGGUUGCACAAGCAAAGGCCUCGUCCUGCCCGCCGUGCUGGGCAUCACCUUUGGUGCCUUCCUCAUCGGGGCCCUGCUCACUGCUGCACUCUGGUACAUCUACUCGCACACGCGUGAGUACCCCAGGCCCCCACAGUGAGCAUGCCGGGCCCCUCCAUCCACCCGGGGGAGCCCAGUGAAGCCUCUGAGGGAUUGAGGGGCCCUGGCCAGGACCCUGACCUCCGCCCCUGCCCCCGCUCCCGCUCCCAGGUUCCCCCAGCAAGCGGGAGCCCGUGGUGGCGGUGGCUGCCCCGGCCUCCUCGGAGAGCAGCAGCACCAACCACAGCAUCGGGAGCACCCAGAGCACCCCCUGCUCCACCAGCAGCAUGGCAUAGCCCCGGCCCCCCGCGCUCGCCCAGCAGGAGAGACUGAGCAGCCGCCAGCUGGGAGCACUGGUGUGAACUCACCCUGGGAGCCAGUCCUCCACUCGACCCAGAAUGGAGCCUGCUCUCCGCGCCUACCCUUCCCGCCUCCCUCUCAGAGGCCUGCUGCCAGUGCAGCCACUGGCUUGGAACACCUUGGGGUCCCUCCACCCCACAGAACCUUCAACCCAGUGGGUCUGGGAUAUGGCUGCCCAGGAGACAGACCACUUGCCACGCUGUUGUAAAAACCCAAGUCCCUGUCAUUUGAACCUGGAUCCAGCACUGGUGAACUGAGCUGGGCAGGAAGGGAGAACUUGAAACAGAUUCAGGCCAGCCCAGCCAGGCCAACAGCACCUCCCCGCUGGGAAGAGAAGAGGGCCCAGCCCAGAGCCACCUGGAUCUAUCCCUGCGGCCUCCACACCUGAACUUGCCUAACUAACUGGCAGGGGAGACAGGAGCCUAGCGGAGCCCAGCCUGGGAGCCCAGAGGGUGGCAAGAACAGUGGGCGUUGGGAGCCUAGCUCCUGCCACAUGGAGCCCCCUCUGCCGGUCGGGCAGCCAGCAGAGGGGGAGUAGCCAAGCUGCUUGUCCUGGGCCUGCCCCUGUGUAUUCACCACCAAUAAAUCAGACCAUGAAACCA